AUGCUAAAACUAAUCGUCCCAACAAUUAUAUUACUACCACUGACAUGACUUUCCAAAAAACACAUAAUUUGAAUCAACACAACCACCCACAGCCUAAUUAUUAGCAUCAUCCCUCUACUAUUUUUUAACCAAAUCAACAACAACCUAUUUAGCUGUUCCCCAACCUUUUCCUCCGACCCCCUAACAACCCCCCUCCUAAUACUAACUACCUGACUCCUACCCCUCACAAUCAUGGCAAGCCAACGCCACUUAUCCAGUGAACCACUAUCACGAAAAAAACUCUACCUCUCUAUACUAAUCUCCCUACAAAUCUCCUUAAUUAUAACAUUCACAGCCACAGAACUAAUCAUAUUUUAUAUCUUCUUCGAAACCACACUUAUCCCCACCUUGGCUAUCAUCACCCGAUGAGGCAACCAGCCAGAACGCCUGAACGCAGGCACAUACUUCCUAUUCUACACCCUAGUAGGCUCCCUUCCCCUACUCAUCGCACUAAUUUACACUCACAACACCCUAGGCUCACUAAACAUUCUACUACUCACUCUCACUGCCCAAGAACUAUCAAACUCCUGAGCCAACAACUUAAUAUGACUAGCUUACACAAUAGCUUUUAUAGUAAAGAUACCUCUUUACGGACUCCACUUAUGACUCCCUAAAGCCCAUGUCGAAGCCCCCAUCGCUGGGUCAAUAGUACUUGCCGCAGUACUCUUAAAACUAGGCGGCUAUGGUAUAAUACGCCUCACACUCAUUCUCAACCCCCUGACAAAACACAUAGCCUACCCCUUCCUUGUACUAUCCCUAUGAGGCAUAAUUAUAACAAGCUCCAUCUGCCUACGACAAACAGACCUAAAAUCGCUCAUUGCAUACUCUUCAAUCAGCCACAUAGCCCUCGUAGUAACAGCCAUUCUCAUCCAAACCCCCUGAAGCUUCACCGGCGCAGUCAUUCUCAUAAUCGCCCACGGGCUUACAUCCUCAUUACUAUUCUGCCUAGCAAACUCAAACUACGAACGCACUCACAGUCGCAUCAUAAUCCUCUCUCAAGGACUUCAAACUCUACUCCCACUAAUAGCUUUUUGAUGACUUCUAGCAAGCCUCGCUAACCUCGCCUUACCCCCCACUAUUAACCUACUGGGAGAACUCUCUGUGCUAGUAACCACGUUCUCCUGAUCAAAUAUCACUCUCCUACUUACAGGACUCAACAUACUAGUCACAGCCCUAUACUCCCUCUACAUAUUUACCACAACACAAUGGGGCUCACUCACCCACCACAUUAACAACAUAAAACCCUCAUUCACACGAGAAAACACCCUCAUGUUCAUACACCUAUCCCCCAUUCUCCUCCUAUCCCUCAACCCCGACAUCAUUACCGGGUUUUCCUCUU